GGGCGGGAGGAGCCGCUCGCCGGUUUUGCCGCCUCCGCCUUUGCCUUCGCAGCCGCCUCCAGGUAAGGGGGCCCCGGAGGAGCCGCCAGGCCACGGUGGCGCGCACCUCGCUGGGCCACUCCCCGCCGGCCCCACGCGGGGCACUCGGAGCCCGGCCCAGCCCCGGGGCCCUUUGCCCUGCGCCCCGCCCUCCACCCCGGGGACACUGGACCCACCAGGAAGCGGCCGCGCGCUCCCUGGCGCUGCCUGCCCUAAGCCCAGGCCGCCUGCUGGUGGUUGGUUUGUUUUCAGAGCCGGAAGUGCUUUUAGAAAUCUUGGGGAGGCAGAGGGGGAAACUGAGGCUGGGCGGAGCACUCGGGCGACUCCGGCCUCGGCCUCCGAGUUCUUAGAGGUCACCCAGCCGCUCCCUUGACAAAUGAGGACGCUGGUCAAGACUCUCAAACAGAGAAUUCCAGGAGGGCUUGGGGAGCCUCUGGAGAAAAACCAGGCUCCUCAUGUUACAAGGAGGCCAUGUCUUCUGGUGCCCAUGCCUGAAGUUACAGGAGGGAAGAAUUACUGCUGCUGACUUUUGAGUGGAUUUUACAGCUGGGUAAACUGAGGCUCAGAGAGUGUUGUACAUUAUAAACCGGGGCUGCUGAUGAGGAGUGGGGAACUGGCUCUCUGGAACGUGUGACAGCAGGCAGAAGGGUGUGAUUAUCCAAAACCCUCUGGGUUCUUCUACGUUGGAACUGUUGUCAUGGAGACCUCCUGAGAUGCCUCACUGACCUCUCGCUUCCAAUAUGACUUCAGAUAGAGAUGUAGAAUCAAUGGGUGUCUCUUCUAAAUGGCUGCAGAGGGUGCUGACCUGGGCCUGCCUAGACUCUGCCCUUCUAGGAGCAUCUCAAGAUUGUCUUAUUUUGGGUGUGGGCAAUUUGCAUAUUUCUCCAAAGAACCAUCCAGAACCUGAGCAGCCUGUCUUCAGACAGAGAGAGGCCCACGGCUGUUUCUUGAAAUCUGGUGAUCCAGGUCCUGUCCAGAAAGCUCGGGGUGUGGCAGUGAAAAAACAACCAGGGAACUGCCUCGUACACACAGCGCUGGGAAUGGCCAUGUGGAACAGGCCAUGCCAGAGGCUGCCUCAGCAGCCUCUGGUAGCUGAGCCCACUGCAGAGGGGGAGCCACACCUGCCCACGGGCCGGGAGCUGACUGAGGCCAACCGCUUCGCCUAUGCUGCCCUCUGUGGCAUCUCCCUGUCCCAGUUAUUUCCUGAACCCGAACACAGCUCCUUCUGCACAGAGUUCAUGGCAGGCCUGGUGCAGUGGCUGGAGUUGUCUGAAGCUGUCUUGCCAACCAUGACUGCUUUUGCGAGCGGCCUGGGAGGUGAAGGAGCAGAUGUGUUUGUUCAAAUUUUACUGAAGGACCCCAUCUUGAAGGACGACCCGACGGUGAUCACUCAGGACCUUCUGAGCUUCUCACUCAAGGAUGGGCACUAUGACGCCCGGGCCAGAGUCCUCGUUUGCCACAUGACCUCCCUGCUCCAAGUGCCCUUGGAGGAGCUGGAUGUCCUUGAAGAGAUGUUCCUGGAGAGCCUGAAGGAAAUCAAAGAAGAGGAAUCUGAAAUGGCCGAGGCAUCCCGAAAGAAGAAAGAAAACCGGAGGAAAUGGAAGCGUUAUCUCCUGAUAGGCCUGGCGACUGUCGGAGGCGGAACGGUGAUCGGUGUGACUGGAGGUCUAGCUGCACCCCUUGUUGCCGCUGGAGCAGCGACGAUUAUUGGCAGCGCCGGGGCAGCGGCUCUGGGCUCAGCAGCCGGCAUAGCCAUCAUGACCUCGCUGUUUGGUGCAGCUGGAGCUGGCCUGACAGGAUACAAGAUGAAGAAGCGAGUGGGAGCCAUUGAAGAGUUCACGUUUCUGCCUCUGACGGAGGGCAGGCAGCUGCACAUCACCAUCGCCGUCACGGGGUGGCUCGCUUCUGGCAAAUACCGCACCUUCAGUGCCCCGUGGGCUGCCCUGGCCCACAGCCGUGAGCAGUACUGCCUGGCCUGGGAAGCCAAGUACCUGAUGGAGCUCGGCAAUGCCCUGGAGACCAUCCUCAGUGGUCUCGCCAACAUGGUGGCCCAGGAGGCCCUAAAGUACACAGUGUUGUCUGGCAUUGUGGCUGCCCUGACCUGGCCAGCCUCACUCCUCAGUGUCGCCAAUGUCAUCGACAACCCCUGGGGGGUGUGUCUCCAUCGAUCAGCAGAGGUUGGCAAGCACCUGGCCCACAUCCUGCUCUCCCGGCAGCAGGGGCGACGACCUGUCACCUUGAUUGGCUUCAGCCUGGGAGCCAGAGUCAUCUACUUCUGUCUGCAGGAGAUGGCUCAAGAGAAAGAUUGCCAAGGAAUCAUCGAGGACGUCAUCCUGCUGGGUGCGCCUGUGGAGGGAGAAGCCAAGCAUUGGGAGCCUUUCCGGAAGGUGGUGUCCGGGAGGAUCAUCAACGGCUACUGCAGGGGAGACUGGCUGCUGAGUUUCGUGUACCGCACAUCCUCGGUGCAGCUCCGUGUCGCCGGCCUACAGCCCGUGCUGCUGCAGGACAGGAGGGUGGAGAACGUGGACCUGACCUCUGUGGUCAGCGGCCACCUGGACUAUGCCAAGCAGAUGGAUGCCAUCCUGAAGGCCGUGGGCAUCCGCACCAAGCCAGGCUGGGACGAGAAGGGGCUCUUGCUGGCCCCAGGCUGCCUGCCCUCCGAGGAGCCUCGCCAGGCAGCAGCUGCCGCCUCAUCAGGCGAGACCCCCCACCAGGUUGGGCAAACCCAGGGUCCCAUAUCCGGAGACACCUCCAAAUUGGCCAUGUCCACAGACCCCAGCCAAGCCCAGGUGCCAGUAGGGCUGGACCAGUCUGAAGGGGCCUCCCUUCCUGCUGCUGCCAGCCCUGAAAGGCCCCCCAUCUGCAGCCAUGGCAUGGACCCCAACCCACUGGGCUGCCCCGAUUGUGCCUGCAAGACCCAGGGCCCCAGCACGGGGCUGGACUGACCACAGCAGGGGACCUGAGCCGUCUUCCCCAGUCUCCAUAUGCAGCUCUCUCUUAUACCCUCGGGUUCCUCCCAGGAGCUCUGGAGGUACAGGAUUUCCACAGGCCUCUUUCCUAAAUGGAAGGAAUUGGAACUGAAAGGGAAAGGAAAUGGAAGGAAGGGGAAUUUGGAGGAGAGAACACGCCCACCCUUGGGAAGCUGCCUGUCCCCAGAGGAGCCCCACCAGGGAGCAGCUGCCCCCUCAUCAGAGACCUGCAGAGUCAACCAAGCACAGGUUAGAGUCCCAGGACCGGAAACCAACUGUGGGCUUUCUGUACUUCUCAUAGCUUUGGAGUCUGGCUGUCCAUCAGGAGGUCCCGAGGGCUCUCUGGGGCCUGAGGCUCCCACACCAGCUCUCCCCUGGCCUCAAUAAAACCAGGUGCAUGCCUGUUCUUCCAUCCACACUCCAGGGCUGCCCACCAGCUGACAGGCACCAUCAACUGGCAGCAACAGAGCAGGCGCAGGUACAAAGAAGGCAGCUCACUCCUGCUCUUAGGAGAUCCAAUCAGAUCUGCCCUGUACAGCCAUGUAGGCUGUGCGCUGCAUAACUCCAGGGACAUGAGUCACACAGACACAAUGUGAGUGUGCUCCCCCGUCAUGCAACAUCUGGACACCACUAACAGAGCAUGGUGAAUACAUGCUGAAUUGCAUUCAGUAUGGCUGUGAACUAGGCCUGGGGACAAGAAUGAAUUUUACAUGGAAAGAAUUUCCUGUAGCAGGAACAGAGGGGAUAACAACAGCAAUAAAUAAUAAUAAGAAGAA